GCCUCGCCACCAGAGGUUUCCCAGAGAGGAAGGCGUGGCUCCCUCCCGGGCCAGUGAGCCCUGGCGCCGCCGCGGCCGCGGUCCCAGCAGCGGAGUAGGGCGGCGGCUGCGCCCCGCACCAUGGGGGGCAGCCCAGCCCCAGCCGCGGUAAACGCCGACCUCCGCCGCCGCCCGCGCCGCGUCUGCCCCCUCCCGCUGCGGCUCUCUGGACGCCAUCCCCUCCUCACCUCGAAGCCAACAUGAAGGAGACCCGGGGCUACGGAGGGGAUGCCCCCUUCUGCACCCGCCUCAACCACUCCUACACAGGCAUGUGGGCGCCCGAGCGUUCCGCCGAGGCGCGGGGCAACCUCACGCGCCCUCCAGGGUCUGGCGAGGAUUGCGGAUCGGUGUCCGUGGCCUUCCCGAUCACCAUGCUGCUCACUGGUUUCGUGGGCAACGCACUGGCCAUGCUGCUCGUGUCGCGCAGCUACCGGCGCCGGGAGAGCAAGCGCAAGAAGUCCUUCCUGCUGUGCAUCGGCUGGCUGGCGCUCACCGACCUGGUCGGGCAGCUUCUCACCACCCCGGUCGUCAUCGUCGUGUACCUGUCCAAGCAGCGUUGGGAGCACAUCGACCCGUCGGGGCGGCUCUGCACCUUUUUCGGGCUGACCAUGACUGUUUUCGGGCUCUCCUCGUUGUUCAUCGCCAGCGCCAUGGCCGUCGAGCGGGCGCUGGCCAUCAGGGCGCCGCACUGGUAUGCGAGCCACAUGAAGACGCGUGCCACCCGCGCUGUGCUGCUCGGCGUGUGGCUGGCCGUGCUCGCCUUCGCCCUGCUGCCGGUGCUGGGCGUGGGCCAGUACACCGUCCAGUGGCCCGGGACGUGGUGCUUCAUCAGCACCGGGCGAGGGGGCAACGGGACUAGCUCUUCGCAUAACUGGGGCAACCUUUUCUUCGCCUCUGCCUUUGCCUUCCUGGGGCUCUUGGCGCUGACAGUCACCUUUUCCUGCAACCUGGCCACCAUUAAGGCCCUGGUGUCCCGCUGCCGGGCCAAGGCCACGGCAUCUCAGUCCAGUGCCCAGUGGGGCCGCAUCACGACCGAGACGGCCAUUCAGCUUAUGGGGAUCAUGUGCGUGCUGUCGGUCUGCUGGUCUCCGCUCCUGAUAAUGAUGUUGAAAAUGAUCUUCAAUCAGACAUCAGUUGAGCACUGCAAGACACACACGGAGAAGCAGAAAGAAUGCAACUUCUUCUUAAUAGCUGUUCGCCUGGCUUCACUGAACCAGAUCUUGGAUCCUUGGGUUUACCUGCUGUUAAGAAAGAUCCUUCUUCGAAAGUUUUGCCAGGUAGCAAAUGCUGUCUCCAGCUGCUCUAAUGAUGGACAGAAAGGGCAGCCUAUCUCAUUAUCUAAUGAAAUAAUACAGACAGAAGCAUGAAAGAAAACACUUAACUUGCAUGUGCACAGCUUUUGGUAACAAAUAUCGCUAAACCUUACUGUGAAUUUAGGCAUCUCUGGCAUGCCACUGUUUAUGCAUUGAAGUGGAAUUUUUGGUAUAAAGCUAAAUGGUCUUAGAAGCAUAGAAAAUCCCUAUGUGCCAAAAGUAGUGAAACACAAACAAAGGAAAAUAUAUUAAUAACAGUCUAGUGUUUUUGUUGAGUCUGCCAUUCGUAGCUGAAUAUGUGAUUAAUUAUGUGAUGAAAACAUUUUUUAUAAAUGAUCUUGGUCUAUUGGGGAGCGGGGAUAGUUAAUAUUCCAGUACACUGAAUACAUGAGGAAUUUAACCACAUACAUCAUUGAAGACAAGGGAUAGCAGUUUGUUUUUAUUCAAAGACAUUGCUGUGUUCUCUUUCAUUGCCUCUCUCGCUUUCUGUCACUUUUUUCCUCCUUACAUUAAAGAAAAGUUUAAUUACAGUUAAAAAUGUAUAAUGUAUUUAUAAUAUUCAUCGAUACCAUUAUUCAAAUAUUGCUCAAUACAGCAAAUUAGCUCCUAACCUAACAAAGUUUAAGUUUACUUGGAUUGAUAAUUAGGUUUACUCUUUAUCUGAAUAAGAACCAAUUCCAUUUGUUUGAAAUAUGGAGUUUGUGACUACCCAAAUUGCUAAUUAUUCUUUCUUUUGAAUAUAUUUUACAUUUCUAUGAGCCUAAGGAAGAUUCAUGAAACUGACCUAUGAGAGUCGUGAAGUGGUUUUUCAGAAUGCUAUGUAAGGACCGAUUUGAGCACUAACUAUAGGUACUCUGAAUAUAUAUUUCCCUUGAUUAUUCACCAAAAGUGUUCCCCAGUCUUUGACUCUUUAAAUUCCAAUACUGAUUCCAAAACAAAUAAAUAUUUUGAAGACUCAAUGAAUACUUUCCAUAUUUUGGCCUAUUUAUAUAAGAAAGUUAAUAACAUUGACCCUUCACAGCUCUUCUGCCUGCUCCUCAAAGUGGCUCUAUCUAAAUAUUUAUUACUAAAAUGUUUUUCCUACAGUCUACAUGAAUACAAACCUCAAUAGCUAAGCUUGACGUAUUUGUGCACAAGUAGAUCACUACAUUAAGUUUUGGGAAUUGCACUUCUUAAAAAUGUCUCCCCACCAAACAUAGUAAUCCUGUAGUUAUGCCUACACAAAGCUUGCCAUAUUCUUUGGUGCAUUCAUUUUGUAAACCCAUUAACUUUUUAUUGUGAAGAUUUUCAUUUGCAGUUUCUUGCACUGCUUUUCUAGUUUUUUAAAAGCUUGAGAUUUAUUUAUACUUCUUGUAGUAACUGCAUAUUUCUGUGUGUGUUUAGUGGUAAAGAAUUAAUUUUGAUAGGUACAAUAUGUCUAUCAGAUUGAUAUAUACACCAGCCUAUGUCAAUUGGGGCUAAUUAUUUUAAAUGACCAUGUCAAAUUGAAUUUGGAGACAAAAUCUGUUGAGAGUGCUUAUGUAAUUAAUGAUGGUUCUACUAAUCUAAAUUUUGGAAAAGGUGAUAAAUAGACUAUACUAAAAUCUCUCUAUGCCAUAGAAUUGGAUUAUCCUGUAGGUCAUCUCAUUGGGUAUAAGACAAAACUACCUACUUUUUUUCAAAAGUGCACUGAAAUCACAUAAUAAAGAGGCUUUACCUCUUGGUUGGUCCUGUGACCCUAAGUUCUAGUCAGAUAGACACAGAGGCAAUGUGAAUUUGAGUGGCAUGAGCAUGAUUAGGUUAUUCCUUCCAGCAUCUAGUAUAGCACCUGGAAUAUAGAAACUGUCUAAUACAUAUUUAUUCAGUGAAUCAAUGAGCAGAAGUUUGCCAGGACAGUACACAUUGGCAAGGCACAUACCAUAUGAUUGAAGUGCUUCAUGCCAUUACAGUCCAUCAGGCUGAUAAAGUGAAUUAUUUCUGAUUAUUUAAUUACAGAAAUAUGAAUUUAUCUUCAAGGGUGUAGUGUCAUACUGCUGUACAACACAGUGCUUUAUUUAUACUAAUAAUUUAGGAGACUGAUACUUCCAAAUGAUAGUGGACAUUACUAUCACAAGAAUAUCACUUUUCAUCAAACUGCAAAAAUACAGAAAGGCAAAAAACCUGACACUUAUUCUUAACUGCAAAUUAAAUUCCUGCCCAGGGGAUAUAUUUUAGGAGGGGAUGAAUGGCAGCUUUUGUGUUUUUUUUAACAAGCUUGAAAGGGAGGUGGAAAACAAAGAAAUUAUGUAAAUGGCAUAUGAGUUUUAUUAUCUAGGCAUUCGUUAGUAUGGGGAAACCUGAUAAGAAAUGAAAAUCCCAAAUGAUUUCAGCCUUUUCAUGAUGGUUGAGGUUAGAUUUCAGAGAUGUACAGAGACUAGAGCGGUGGUUAGAAAGAGGAUAUAUGUAGUCACAGCAGAAAGACGUGUCUAAGUUUAAUUUUAUUGGCUUUCAAGUUCACUCAUGUAUACUUAGUUUGUCCAUACAUAUGUCUAAUCAGGAAAAAUGCAUGUAUAGAUUAUGACAAUUCCUGAAUUUUGAAGUAUUGGUUAAAAGACAAUUAAAGGCCAAGAAAACCAUGGUGGAAGAAGUAAGCGAAUGAAAUGUAGAAAUAUAUGUAAAAUUAGCAAGUGUCAAUUUUACCAAGUAGUGUUGAUUUUCCAAACAAUGAAUUUAUAUACUAUGCUGAGUCACAGAGAAGAAUGAUCACAUGUUACUUAAUGAGAGCAGUUUACUUUUCAAAUAAAAUAGGUAUGAUGAAUGUCUUAAAAAUAUCUUGAAGUUGAAGAAACAAAAAUGAGUUAUCUCAAUAUUUACCAAGUUAACCUAGUGCUGUAUAUAUCCCAAGAUAUUUUAGGUAAAUGUAAGUGUUUAAUCAUGCCAGAUUUAAACUAGUCUGAAAUAUAGGGUAUACAUAUAUUUCUACUUACAUUUCUUUAUUUUAUGAAAUAUCCGACCAUGUUGCAGAAAAUAAUGCAAAACCUCAUGUAAGUUAACUAUGAAAGAUCCUGUGAGCACAUUGGCAUUGAGUGACAGACAAACUAAAAACUGGCAAACAGUAUUUUAAUAAGGGGGUCACUCUGUGGCAGUAUUCUAAUAUUGGAUUUUCAAGUAGAUUAGGCUUUUUAUUUAUUCAACGCUUUUUAUAAUUUUGUUCUUUUUGACUCCAAAUUAUUGGUCAGCUUUCAACCUUCUCCACAUCAGCAAUCACUAAUAGUUCUUUUGGUUGAGAUCAACUCAGAAAAAGAAAAUAGAAAACUUUUGUUCUUUGAAAUUUUAGACAUGCAUAAUAUCUAUUUAUUUUCAUAAUUUAACCCCAAAAGCUUCUCCUGCAAUACACAGGAUUCUAGGAGCUGAAUGACACAGGGAGACUACAGAGUAUUUAUUAUUACAAACACAUAAAAAGCCUAACUUGAAGAAUUAAAAUUUCUAUUUUUUAUCUGUAUAACAAGUACAAACCAUCAACAAUGACAAAUUUUCACAGCUGCUUGUUUAUUGCUUGUUUUAUAUGUUUACAUAUCUCAAAAUCUGUUAAAACUGAGGUCUAAAAAAUGUGCAGAAUUGUGCAACUGUGGCCUAGUCCAUAAGACUUUUCUGAGUUGCAACAAAGUGCUGACAAAGUGACAGAUGUCUGUGAUGUUUCAUGACAUAGGUUAUGAUCGAGCCAAUUUACAAAAUUUAAUAACCAACCUAAACUCACAUACAUAUUUGUUAAGAAGCUGACAUCAGUUCAGUAUUGUAAGGAAACUAACUAGGUGGUGAUGAUGAUAAAAGAAUUAGGGAAAAUAUUUUAUUUGAUAUAUUCCCUUUUAUAAUUCCUAAAAUGAAGAUUCUAUUUAAGGGUUAUAAUUUAUAUAAGUUUAGUCAUAUACCAUUACAUUAUGAUACCAUAAGCAGAGUGCAUUAUGAUUCUCUAGAAAUAUAAUUCAAUCAGAUAUGUAUUAUAUUUAUUUAUGUCACACAUUUUCUUUACUGAGAAUAAAAAUUAUCUUAUUUUCAGAAGCUUUGUAUCAAUCAGUUUCAUGUAAUAAGCAACCCAGAUAUCUACUAGAUUAUGUAUUUCUUCAUUUGAAACUACACUGUUUUCUCCUAGUCCCCUUGACUCUACUGUGCUUAUCCAUUCUUUCACAGAAAGAAAGUAACAGACAUAAUUCCUGUUGAUGAGGCUGGGAUUGUUUUUAAGAGGAGAGAUAAUAACUUCAUAUUUUUAAAGUGCCAGUAGCCUAAUAUGUGAAACAGAUCAGAAUCUGUUGUGUAGUAAGUCUGCUUUGUUGAAGAAUUUAUUAUGGGAGUAAAGAUAAGAAGGAAAGAGAUCACCAUCAGAAACAAGUCAGCCUUUUCAUGCUUUUUUGAGCAUUUUUGGAGAUGAUUCCACUUCUCAAGUUAUUAUCAUUUGUGCAUCUCUUCAAUGCUAUUGUUAAAUGCUUUAGAAUUAGAAUAUUUUGAUCCUUUAAUUAAAGUAAGCCAAACGUCUAGGCAAAAACAGCCAAUCAUUAAACUUUAAUAGUAAUUCAAAUAUAGAUUUCUCAUACAGUUUUCCAUGUCUGUAGAAAUCAAAGUUGUAAUGUUAAGCAGAGGGAAAUGCGUGUGAUUUACUAAUACACUUCAACGUUCUACUUUUGAAAGGAUACUCAUGUGGGUGGGGCAGAGAACAUAGAAAAAGAUAUGAUGGAAAACCUGUCCAUUUUCUACCUGUUAACCUUCAUCAUUUUGUGCCAGGCCCUGGAAGCAAAGAGAGGAAGGGACCGACUGCAUUUAUCUUUGAACACUUGAGCAUCAGUAGUACUACUGAGUGGCCAGGGGUCUUGUCUGUCAAAGCAAAUGAUAAGUUCACUCAGGCCAUUAUUGACUGCUGAACUCUCUUCCUUCCCAACUCUUCCUUGAAAGAGAAAAAAAUACUUUGCCUUCUUGCUCUCCUUAUCAAAUGUUUUUGUACAAAUAGUGUAAGCCUGUUUAAGCAAACCAAUUAAAAUAGGCACUGAUUAUUUUGAUCUGUUUGUAACAAAUGAAUGUAAGUACUAUUUACAUGGUGUGCCUAGGAGGAGCUGAAAUCAUUGGCACUUUAAUCCAUAUUGUAAAGAUCAGUAUCAAAAGCAUAGUGUUCUUCACCUCUCCUCCUCAGCAUCCAUCUCUAUAUACUUGAUUAAAUGGAAAAGUCUCUUUUAUCACCUCUAUGUAAAGUUUUAUGGGUAGUUAUCGUCAGUGUAUUUAAAUAUAUCUUCUAGUAUGUUUUAAAGGCUGGUCUUCAAUACUGUGGAGACAAAAAAUAAAAGAGCGUAUGAAAAGUACGUUAGACUUUUGCUGGCAUUCAAGUCAUGGCUAGUCUGUGUAUUUAAUAAAUGUGUGUUAUUUAUGUCGUGUUUGUCAAUGGAAAAUAAAGUUGAAUAUUCUGAAAUGUCGCUGUGUUUUCUUCCUGAUGUCAACUCACGUCAGGAAUACUUUACCUAUAACUAUGUUAAGUAUUUUGCUGAAAUCCCAUUUGAUGUGCUUUGUCAAAUAAUAGCACAAUGUAAUGCAACAGCCCCAUGCUAUCUGGAAAAAUUAGAUCAUUUUGUUUUAUAUUCCAUAAUCAUGUGCAUAACAAAUUAUUGUUGAUUUAAUAUAAAUAUGAGAGUUGCUCUUUUCCGAUUUUCAACAUGAUGUUUCUUUGUUUUAUUAUCUCAAGAUUAUUGUUCUUAACACAGAGUGCAUUUAUAAAUUAUUGUAAGCUUAGUUAUUUCCCUUUCUUGUGGAUUUUGGUGUAAUUUACAGGCAGCCAAAAUAAGAAUUGUCCUUGCUCAUAGUACAACCCUUUAAUUGACUUGUGCCUGAGUUUUGGUGUGAGCUGAGUAUUGGUGGUUAUGAAUACUGGGAUCCCCAGCUAUUUGUUCAUGUACUUAUUGAGGUCACUAUUGGUCUUCCUUCUUCAAUGAAGGGAGAAGCUCUGUCAAAUGUAGACUGCAAAGUCAAGCUCAUUAAAAGUAUCCCUCUUUCUUCGUGAGAAAAGAUAUCCAAGGAGAAUUCUGUCCCUGGUUCCUCCCAUGUGGGGGUUCUAGGCCUAGGACCAGAUCUUAUUGUCUCUACAAUCUUGAUUCUUUAGUAUUUCAGGAUAGGCAGAGUUUUGUUAAAGUAUACAAAAAUCAUAGCUAGAUAAGAGAGAUAACAGAAAUAAGUUCCAGUGUUCUAUACUCCUGUAGGAUGACUACAGUUAAUGCUAAUAUACAGUUACAAAUAGCUAGAAGGAGGCUAUUGAAUGUUCCCAACACAAAGAAAUGAUAAAUGUUUGAGAUGAUGAUGUGCUAAUUACCCUCAUCUGACCAGUAUACAUUAUAUGUAUCGAAACAUCGCUCUGUGCCCUGCGAAUAUGUACAAUUGUGAUUAUUAAAAUAAAUACAUAAAUAAAAUUUAAAAGUCA